CUGCAGCUGCCUGAAGGAGCCAUCUCAUCCACAGCUCUUCCUUGAGCAGCCAUGGCCAGCUCCAGGCGAGGCCUCCUGCUCCUGCUGCUGCUGACUGCCCACCUUGGACCCUCAGAGGCUCAGCACUGGUCCCAUGGCUGGUACCCUGGAGGAAAGCGAGCCCUCAGCUCAGCCCAGGAUCCCCAGAAUGCCCUUAGGCCCCCAGGAAGGGCCCUGGACACUGCAGCAGGCAGCCCAGUCCAGACUGCCCAUGGCCUCCCAAGUGAUGCCCUGGCUCCCCUGGACGACAGCAUGCCCUGGGAGGGCAGGACCACGGCCCAGUGGUCCCUUCACAGGAAGCGACACCUGGCACGGACACUGCUGACCGCAGCCCGAGAGCCCCGCCCCGCCCCGCCAUCCUCCAAUAAAGUGUGAGGUUCUCCGAA